GUGGCGGCUGCUGCAGAGCCGCCAGGAGGAGGGUGGAUCUCCCCAGAGCAAAGCGUCGGAGUCCUCCUCCUCCUUCUCCUCCUCCUCCUCCUCCUCCUCCAGCCGCCCAGGCUCCCCCGCCACCCGUCAGACUCCUCCUUCGACCGCUCCCGGCGCGGGGCCUUCCAGGCGACAAGGACCGAGUACCCUCCGGCCGGAGCCACGCAGCCGCGGCUUCCGGAGCCCUCGGGGCGGCGGACUGGCUCGCGGUGCAGGCUGUACUGGCAUGACACCAACAUCUGCUUGGCGAGUUGAGGCCUCAGGAAGUUUUUACUCAUGGAAGAAGGCGAAGGGUGAGCAGGUGUGACACAUGGCAAAAGAAGAGUGAGAGAGAGGAGGAGGUUCUGGGCUCUUUUAAACAACCAGCUCUCAUGUGAACUAAUAGAGUAAGAACUUGCUCAUUACUGUGAGGACAGCACCAAGCCAUUCGUGAGGAAUCUGCCCUAUGACGGAAACAUCCCCCGACUAGGCCCGCCUCCAACCUUGGGAAUUACAUUUCAACAUGAAACUUGGAAGAGACACACAUCCAAAUCAUAUCAAUUACUUCCAUCAUUGCUUCUCUCAGACUUUCCAGAUAUACUAUUGUGUCAUCUGUAAAUAGUUUUUUUUCCUUCUUUUCCAGUGUUUAUGCCUUUAACUAUUUAUCUAAUUGCACUGACUAAUAUCUCCAGAACAAGAUUAAAUAGCAGUGUAACAAUGUCUUUAAUAGAGGUACUGAUUGCUUCAUUGUAUUAUCUUCACCAUGGAUAUACAAAUGUGUACAUUUCAAUGUAGAUAAUAGUUUGGCUAUGUAUAUACCUUACAAGGGUUGCACACAGUCCUUCGCUGUGUCUUUAAGAGAUGCUUAUGGAGAUUGGCUGGGCGUGGUGGCUAAGGCCUGUAAUCCCAGUACUUUGGGAGGCUGAGGCUAGCAGGUAGCUUGAGCUCAUGAGUUUGAGACCAGGUCGAGUAAGAUGGUGAAACCCUGUCUCUACAAAAAGUACAAAAAUUAGCUAAGUAUGGUGGCAUGUGCUUGUGGUCCCAGCUACUAGGGAGCUGAGGUGGGAGGAUCACUUGAGCCCAGGAGGGGAGGCUUCAAUGAGCUGAGAUCAUGCCACUGCACUCCAGGCUGGGUGACAGAGUGAGACCCCAUCUCAAUUUUUAAAAAAUUAAAUUUUAACAAAAGAUACUUAAGGAGAUGGAUGUGGUAAGAAGCAGGAAAGGUCAACUUUCCUAGUGCAUGGUAGGAAAAUACGGUGUUUAGCAUGGUAACUGCUCCAUGGUUUCUCAGUUUAUACAAGCAGCCCUGAGUUUUCUUGCUUCUCUACACAGUUUUCUGGAUUUCAUUUUGUUUUUUACCCAGCUAGUUAUAGAUGCCACAGGGUGACCUCCUUUUCCCUUCUAGGCUAAAGCUGUCAUAGGUCUAUGAAAAUCUAGGGAUUCCCUUCUAGGCUUCACAGUCUUAAGUGGUGUGUGUGCUUUGCAGAUGAGCAAGGCUUGUUUUGUAUUGAUAUGUUGCUGCCUUGACUUCUUGGAUUUCUAGAUCAUAUAGCAAGGUAAAUGUUAGUCUGUUCUCGCACUGCUAUAAAGACAUACCCGAGAAUGGGUAAUUUAUAAAGAAAAGAGGUUUAAUUAACUCACAGUUCCACAUGGCUGGGGAGGCCUCAGGAAACUUAAAAUCAUGGCAGAAGAUGAAGCAGACGUGUCUUACAUGUCAGCAGAAAAGAGAGAGAAGGGGAGAGAGAGAAUGAGAAUUCAUGAGAGUGAGCAGGAGCGAGCAUGUGCAUGCAAGAGCAGGAAAAACUGCCUUAUAAAACCAUCAGAUCUCGUGAGAACUCACUGUCACGAGAACAGCAUGGAGGAAACUGCUUCCAUGAUCCAGUCACCUCCCACCUAGUCCCUCCCUCAACAAGUGGGGUUAUGGCGAUUAUAAUUCAAGAUGAGAUUUUGGUGGGGACACAGCCACACCCUAUCAGCAGGUUUGUAAUUAGAUGAGUUUAUCCACUGGGGGGUAAUCCUAGAGUACAUAUCUGUGGGUGGUUCUUGACAAGUGUGUAAGGCCUGGGACAUCUGGCUUUGAGGCAGUUCUUUCUCCAGGUUUUAUUUAUGCGAAUCCACUCAUCUGGCAGGAAUGAUUUGUUGGUGUGAAAUCAGGUGUUGGCCCAGCAUCCUGCACAUGUUCCAUCCACAUGGCAGUGAUGGUCAUUGCACACCAGUGCUUGGUCUCCCAAGUUCUGGAGAGUGUUUUUAUUUCACUGCCAUCUAAUUUAUCCAGAAAGUUCAAGUAGCGUAUUUUCUGUAGAUUCUUAUAAUUUCAAGAUUACCAGGUCCCUGUGUGAACUCUCAGACCACAUCCUGUUGCCUUUCUCUGUCAUUCUAUUGUUUUCUCUCCCAGGAGGGCUGGGUGGUAGGGUAUUUAUUAAUUUAUUGCCCCAUAUACUAAUGAGUUCCUUCCUAGAACUCCUUACAACUCUCAGUCCAUGGCCUGUUGUCCAUCUUUGCUGUCCCAGGAGUGCUGGUAGGUAGAGUAUUUAAUGAUCUCUUCUUGUCCCUAGGUUGAGGAGCCCUCACUCACCUUGGUCCAUUCCUUGGUCCAUUCCAGCUGUCUGUUUUCACUUUUCCUGUGACCCAUGUCACCUUUUUCUCUCUGGGUCUUGCUGCCUCACUGGUAUGAAAUUCAGACUUGGGUGGGGCAGACUUGGGGGUUUCCUGCCUUGAAGAUCCUCAGAUCUUGUCCUGUGGUACAUGCAGCUACCCUGAUGGCACACUUCAGCAGGAGGGUGAUCUUUUCUGUUCUUUUUUGUUGUUGUCUUAUUUCCUCUGCCUGCCCCCACCAUUUUUAGUCUGAGGGAAAUCUGUCUUCCAUCAUCUUUCUGCCUAAAAUAUUUAGUCCAUCCCCAGAAGUCUUAGGUUUCUGGGACACCAGCCCUAGUCAUUUAAUGUUUGAAUAAUUGGUAACCUUCCCACUACCCUAUUAAUCUCCAAGGUCUUCCUAUUUCUUAUGUCUACAUAAUACAGCUAAGACAAUUCUCGGUGCCUGCUACUUCAUUCUUAUUUGCUGCUUGUGAUUUUCAGUAGCUUUCUUAGUCCCUAAGAAUAAAAUAAAACUUGAUCAUUUUGUUGCUAUUUGUUGCCAUUUGUUGCUAUGCUUAUUUAUUUUUAUGUUUUGUUUUGAUCCAGUUCAUAAAAUCCAUUUCUUUGUUUUGUUAAAGUUUCUACUUAUCUGGUUACAACUGCUUGUCUUUUUUGCACAUUCAUUGGUCAUUUAUAUUUCUUAGCCUGUGAAUUGUCUUUAUUUCCUUUGCUUAUUAUUUUUCUGUAGUGAGGACUUGAAUCUUCUUUAUAAUAACAGAUUUAUUGGGAUAUAAUUCACAUACCAUAAAAUUUGCCCUUUUAAAUGUGCAGUUUUGCCAGGUGUGGUGGCUCACGCCUGUAAUUCCAGCACUUUGGGCAGCCAAGGCAGGCAGAUUGCUUGAGUCCAGGAGUUCAACAUGGCAAAACCCCAUCUCUGCAAAAAAUAGAAAAAAAUUAGCCAAGCAUCUCUACAAAAAAUACAGAAAAAUCAGCCGAGCAUGGUGGCGCGUGCCUGUCUGUAGUCCUAGCUACUCGGGAUGCUGAGGUGGGAGGAUCGCUUGAGCCCAGGAGGUGGAGGUUGCAGUGAGCCGAGAUCGUGCCACUACACUCCAGCCUGGGCAACAGAGCCAGACCUGUCUCGAAAAAGAAAAAGUACAAUUUAGUGGUUUUUAAUAUAGUCAGAGUUGUGCAAUUAUCACCAAUAUCUAAUUCCAGAACAUUUUCAUUACUUUCAAAAAGAAAGCCAUACUCAUUAGUCAUCAGUCCUGAUUUCUUCUGCCCCUCAGCCCCUGGCAACUACUAAUCUAUUUUCUCUCUCUACAGCAGUGGUCCCCAACCUUAUUGGCACCAGGGACUGGUUUUGUGGAAGACAGUUUUUCCACGGACCAGGGGAAAUGGGGAGGAGGAUGGCGUUGGGAUGAAACUGUUCCACUUCAAAUCAUCAGGCAUUAGUUAGAUUCUCAUAAGGAGCAUACAAACUAGAUUGCUCAGGUGCACAGUUCACAAUAAGGUUUGUACUCCUAUGAGAAUCUAAUGCCACCACUGAUCUGACAGGAGGUGGAGCUCAGGCAGUAAUGCUUGCUCACCCUCCGCUCACCUCCUGCUGUGCGGCCCAGUUCCUAACAGGCCACAGACUGGUACCAGUUUGUGGCCCAGGGGUUGGGGAGCCUGCUCUACAGACUUGCCUAUUCCAGAUAAUUUUUGGAUUCCAUAAAUGGAGUCAUACAAUAGGUGGUCUUUUGUGUCUGGCUACUUUCACCUAACAUAAUGUUUUCAAGAUCAUCCAUGUUGUAGCAUGCGGCAAUACUUCAUUUGUUCUAAUGGCUGAAUAAUGUUCCAUUGUGUGGGUAUGCCAUAAUUUAUCCAUUCAUCAGUUGAUGGACAUGUGGGUGUUUCUACUUUGGGGCUUAUAUUGAAUAAUGUUGACAUGAACAUUGAUGUAUGUGUUUUUGCAUAGAUGUAUGUUUUCAUUUCUCUUGGGUGUAUAUACCUAGGAGUGGAAGUGCUGGGUCGUAUAAUAACUCCCAUGUUUAACAUUUUGAAGACCAGCCAAACUUCUAAAGCAGCUGCACCAUUUUACAUCCCCACUGGAAGCGUAUGAGAGUUCCCAGUUUUUCCGCAACUUCACUAACAGUUGUUAUUGUCUUAUCUUUUUUAUUAUAGCCAUUCUAGUGAAUAUAAUUUCUGUCUUCCUUCAUCUGCUGGGAUACUUUGAGCUCACCUAUGUUUAUUAAGUUAUCUAUAUUUUAGCAUAUCGUGUAUGCCUUUUCUUCUUAGAUCUCUAAGUUUGAGGUCCAGUCCCAAGAACACUUUCUUCGUUGUAAAAACUAUAAACAUGACUUUUUGUUUGAACUUCCAGGUGGACUUUCUUUUUGAUUCAUCAACAAAAUUUCUGUUUUACGUUUGUGUGUUUGAUGUUAUACUAGUUUGUUCUCUCACUGCUAUAAAGAACUACCUGAGACUGGGUAAUUUAUGAAGAGAAGAGGUUUAAUUGACUCAGAGUUCUGCAAACUUAACAAGAAUCAUGACCGGGAGCCCUCAGGAGACUUACAAUCAUGGCGGAAAGCAAAGGGGAAGCAAGCACAUUCUCAUUAUGGUGGAGCAGGAGAGAGACACGGGGGCAAGGAAGUGCUACACUUUUAAACCAUCAGAUCUCAUGAGAACUCACUAUCACUAGAACAGCAUGGGGGAAACCACCCCCAUGAUCCAGUCACCUCCUACCAGGUCCAUCCCCUGAUGUGGGGAUUACAAAUUGACAUGAGAUUUUGGUGAGGGCACAGAGUCAAACCCUAUCAGAUGAGUUUCAAGCUAUUAAAAACAUUAAAUUGUUAAAAGCACACUGUUAAAAUUUGUGGUAUAGCAAAUAGAAUGUUUAAGAGUAAUGAAGGGGAAUUAUUCAUAGUGAAUACUGACAUUGUCUAAGUGAAUUUUUAGUGCAGUGUUGACUACAUAAUUGAGGAGUCCCAGUUAUAGCCAAAGUAACCCAAAAUGAUGCUAGGUUUAAUCCUAUAUUUCUGUCCCUAUUAACAGGAAGGUACAAAGUGUGACUAAUUUUUUUUAAUGGAACCUGCACUUUUGUAUACAUUAUCCUUGUUUGAUCUUUAUUAUCAGCCAAGAGAUAUAGAGAGGACGGCUAUUCUUCCACAUUUAUUAACCUUCAUUCAACAAUUCUUUUGAACACACCUGUAACUUAAAGAUUUUAGCACCAAUUCAUUAUGUUACUUUGACUUAAGUAAUACUUCAAAAAGUAUUCCUUAACAAUAGCAUUUUUUGUAAAGCUUUAAGUGGUUCAGUCUCUGAAUAAUUAUUUUAUACUUUUAGUUUCAUUUGUUCCCUCUGUUAGUUUCAGUAUGUUAACACAGGUAGACCAAAAAGAUGACAGUAUUUAUACACCAACUAUGUGCUUCUUUCUAAAUGCACAGAUAACUGUAUUGGUGAUUCCAUUUACAUUUGGUUAGGUUUCAAAUGAGAGUGCUAUUUCCUCCCAGCUUUUUGUUUUGAAACAUUUCAAACCUAUAGAAAAGAGUAACAUAGUGUAUUGAAUGCCUACAUACCCUACACCUAUAUUCACCAAUCACCAAUUAUCAUUUUGGCCACAUUUGCUUUUUCUGAGUAUAGAUGCUUUUAUUUAUUGAUUGAUUUUUGAGCUAUUUGAAAGUAAGUUGGAGAAACUUCACCUUUGUGUACUUCAGCUUGCAUUUUCUGAGAAUAAAGGCAUUCUCCUGCAUAAUACUGUUGUAAUACUAUUGUAACACCUAAGAAAAUUAGUAACAAUUCCAUAACAUCCUCUAAUAUCUAACCCAGAUUCAGGUUUCCCAGUUGUCUCCUAAUGUCUCUCUCUUUUUUUAAAAUUUUAUUUUAAAAGACAGGGUCUUAUUCUGUCACUUAGGCUGAAUGCUCUGUCACCUAGGCUGGAGUGCAAUGGUGUGAUCACAGCUCACUCUAACCUCUAACUCCUGGCCUCAAGUGAUCCUGCUGCUUAAGCCUCCUGAGUAGCUGGGAUUACAGGAGUGUGCCAGUUGUUCAUAGAUUUAGAACAAUAUUUAGUGUCAAGUCAGUGAUUUUUCUAAGGUUAUAAUAGGGAUCUUCAUAAAUUUGCCCUUUCCGGAUGGUAGAAAUGAAAUCAUACAAUAUGUGGUUUUUGUGUCUGGCUUCUUUUACUUAGCAUAGUGUCUUUCUGGUUCAUUAAUGUUAAGGCAUGUGUCAGUAGUUCUUUUUUGUUGCUUAGUAGUAUUCUAUUCUAUGGAUAUGGAUAUACCACAUUUUGUUUAUCAUCAUGUCUCCCUGCAGUCUUGACCUCCUGGGCUCAAGCAUUCCUCCCACCUCAGCCUCCCAAGUAGCUGGGACCAGAAGGCACAUGCCACCAGGCCUGGCUAAUUUUUUAAAUUUUUUUGUAGAUAUAGGGUUCUCCCCGUGUUGUCCAGGAUGGUCUGAAACUCCUGGGCUCAAGCAGUCCUCCCCUUUGGCCUCCCAGAAUGCUGGGAUAAUAGGCAUGAGCCACUGUGCCCAGGCCAUCUUGUUUAUCUGUUUAUCAGUUGGUGGACAUUUGGAGUUUUUCCACUUUUUGGUUGUUGUGAAUAAUCCUGCUGUGAACAUUCAUGUACAAGUCUUUGUGUGGACAUAGUUUUCAUUUCUCAUGUAUAUAUACUUGGGAGAGUAAUUAUUGGGUUGUAUGGUACAUUUAUGUUUAACCUCUUAAGAAAUUGCCACACUGUUUUCCAGAGUGGCUGCACAUUACUUUGCAUCCUCACCAGCAGUGUUUGAGGGCUUCUCUUUCUCUGCAUGUUUAUGGACAGUUGUUACACAGUAAGUCCUCACUUAAUGUCAUAGGUAGGUUCUUGGAAAAUGUGACUUUAAGUGAAAUGGUGUAUAACAAAAACAAUUUUACCAUAGGUUAAUUGAUACAAGAGUUAAGUUUCUGUAGCAUAUUUCUGGUCACAAAAACAUCACAAACUUCUAAAUCAAGACCCAAAACACUUCUAAACAUUGAAAGAAUUGUGAGCUUUACAUACCUUUCAGAAAGAUUGAUACAAACAAGUAAGACUAUUACUUAACCCAAUUUUACUCACCCAAUCAGUGAGUGACAGCAGUUGCAUUGGUGGUUGGUCAAAUCAAAGAAGAAAUCUUUACAAAGUGAAAAUUGUAAGGAGAACUUUCUGCCACCACAGUUAAAAAAGAAAUGGCGGUGAUGUGCGCACGUAGUCCCAGCUCCAUGAGAGGCUGAAAUAGGAGGAUCUCUUGAGCCCAAGAGUUUGAGGCUGUAGUGCAUUAUGGUUAAGACUGCAUAGCCAUUGCACUCUUAACCAUGGCAACAUAGUGAGACCCUGUUCCUUUAAAAAGUAGAGGGAGAGAAAUAAUAACAAAUAUGGCAGGCUUUCUGAGCACUUUUAUAUCAUAUCCUGUGUUUUCAUGCAUUUGUCCUAUGAUCAUAGACUUUACAGAUUUUUAUUUUCUGAUAAUUUGUAUUCAUCCAUUCAUUUUCCAACCUGCUUUUUCCAGUUCAGGCUCUUGGAUGGUGAGAGCCUAUUCCAGCAACUCAGGGAACCAGGCUGGAACCAGCCUUGAACAGGACACCGUCCUGUUGCAGGAUGCCCUCAUGCACACACGCACACUCACUCAGACAUGGACAAUUUAGACAUGCCUGUGAACCUCUUAUGCACAUCUUUGCAAUAUGGGUUUUUUUUCCCUUAUUUCAUUAAAACCGAAUCAUGAUGAACCAAACAACAUUAUUUGAGAACCUGCUGUAGUCUUUUUUGACGUUAGUGUUUUUUCUAUAUUAUAACCAUUCUAGUGUGUAUGAAAUGGUAUCUGGUUUUUGUUUUGUUUUGUUUUGAGACAGGGCCUUGCUCUGUUGUUCAGGCUGGAGUGCAGUAGUGAGAUCUUGGCACACUGCAGCUCAGCCUCACAGGUCAAGCAAUCCUACCACCUCAGCCUCCCCAACAGCUGGGACUAUAGGUGCAUGGCAUCACUCCUGGCUAAUUUUUGUAGAAACGGGAUUUUGCCGUGUUGCCCAGGCUUGUCUCAAACUCCUGAGCUCAAGGGAUCCACCCGCCUUGGCCUCCCAAAGUGCUGGGAUUACAGGCAUGAGCCACUGUACCCAGCGUGAAAUGGUAUCUUACUGUGGUUUUCAUUUGCAUUUCCUUAAUAACUGAUGGUGUUCAGCAUCUUUUCAUGUGCUUCUUAGCCAUUCACAUAUCUUCUUUGGUGAGAUGUUUAGUCAAAUCUUUUUCCUGUUUCUUUUUAAAUUGGGUUAUUUAUUUUCUUGUUACUGAGUUGUAAGAGUUUGUUUAUUACAGAUACAAAUCUUACAUCAGAUAUAUAUGAAUGGCAGAUAUUUUCUCUCAGAGAGUGCUAUGUUUUUUUGUAAUGAUGUUGACCAUGAGCCUUUCUUAAUGUUUUCUAAUUUCCCAUGAGACUUUCUUGGAGGCUUGGAAGAAAAGCUAAAUCUUCUGGUCUUAAUUCUUCCAUGUAUCUAUUAAUAGUAUUGAAGCAGAAUCAAUUAAAGAAAGAAUAGUCACCUUCAUCUUCAUUCAACAGUUAAGCAGUGAGAAACUCUUCCCCUUUGGACCAUGUGAAGCAAAUAGUCAUACUGUGGGUAUUAGGACUCUUUCAGUUGUAAGAGCCAGAAAUCCAGUUCAGCAAAACAGAAUUUUGCCAUUUUUUUCCUCUCUUCUUCUACUUCCUUCUCCAUUUUACUGGCAGAUUCUCUUCAUGUGGUCAGGAAUAUAGUCACCUUUAUCUCCAGAUUCAGUUCUUCCCAGCUCAGCAGAGACAGUCUUCCUCACUAGCCCUAUCAGAAGAGCCCAAGAAAUGGAGUGCUUUGGCCAGCUUGAGUCUCAUGCCUUGCUUUUGUGGGAAGUAGCACAUCCUAAUUUAGUCCUGUUGUGAUGGGGUAAGGAGGGGAAGGGGUGCUGGAGGGGUGCUGGGCAGACAAAUCAUAUGUCUACUUCUUUGUGGGUGUUAUAUCAUUUUUGCCCAUUUUUAUGAGGUUAAACCAAAAGUAAUGAAUAGAAGGUUAAUACCUGGACUAUUUUUGAAAACUCAUAUUUAUUUUCUGAUUAAUUUUAACAUUAAAUCAGACUUUACUAAUAGCACCAUUUUCAUAUUGAAACAAACAUAUAUGAUACUUGGUUUAUGCUAAAACAUUCCACAUACAUCUUCCCACCUCCCAAGGAAGGGAGGGGACCUGUAUCAACAAUGAUAACAACUUGAUAAUUGUGGCUGACCUCCCCACUUCUCAUGGACGUUCUUUUAUGUAGUUUUCUUUAGCUCUCUGAGUGGGGUUAUGACCAUCUUGGAGUUCCUAUAUUCCUACAGAUUACUGAAAUCAAUUUUUUGUUAUUGGUUUGCUUCCCCUCUGUUCAUAUAUUUGGAUUCCCAAGCUCUGUCAGUGUCCAUAUGUUAUAUGAUUCAUAUUUGAAGUGAUUUUUGUUUUAAGUAAGGAUAAUUUUUUUUAAGUAAGGAUAAUUCCCAGUUCAUUUUCAUGAUGUUGGGUAUAUGAUGUGGAUGGUGAUGGUGAUGGUGUUAUUGAUGUAGUUUUUGUGAUUUUCUUGCUCAAAAAAGGAAAUCAUUUUUAUCACUUGAAGUGCUUCUUAUCUAAACCCUUAGUAGAUAGAUAUAACUGGAAUUUGUUCAUGUAGUUGAACAGAUAUCUUUGGAUACUGUGUGGAACUUACAUUUCUUCCAUAUAGUACUUUUUGGGAUUUAUUUUAAUAUGAAAAUUAAUUGCAGAAUUGAAAAAUUCUGGCUUGAGAUUAUCUGCAUAAAAUGUAUUAUCUGUCAGAGUUGGAACAGCCCUUAAGGGGUCAUCUUGUAUAUUUUUCUACCCAAGAGAGAGACUAAAGAUCACCUCUACCCAUCUUAGUUCCUCAGUUGGGACAACCGCUGUAACAAAAGGCAAUUUAACAAUAGAAAAACAAGCAUGUGCAGCAUACAACAAGUGGGAGAAACCUCAGUGAAAACGAACUCAGAGCACAGUGGCUUAGAGCUCUGGUUUAUAUAGCAUCUUCAACAAAGAACAGUAAAUGUGUGGGUAAAUGACAGGACAAAGGAAAGGGUUUUAGGCUUCCAGGGGUGGGAAACGGUGGAAAGGUAAAGAUAUAGGGGGAAAGUAAAGGAGUAAGAUUUGUUUGCAGAUUCCUCUGGUGCUGUCUCUGGGCUGAUGAGUCUAGAGUUGUCUCUAGUAACAGAAUUUAUAUCCUAUAUCCUGCCUUUAGGUAGAAAAGAGAGAGGGUAGAGAUAGAUUUUCCUUGGUUUGCUAUCUCUCAGUUGUCUUCAUCUAAAAAGUAAUGUUUGCAUCAAAGAGGCAUAUUUUGGGGUUAUAUAUUCUGAUUUCCUUCACACUCUUUACAAAAAUCCCCUCAAAACUAUCCAGCUAUUAGCCAUUCGUAAACCCCUGUAGUGAUAUUGUGGAAAUCUGCUUCAUUUUUGGAUGUUUAUAUUUAAAAAUAUGUCCUCUUUGAACUGAAGACUGUUGUGACUUCUCUUUAUUCCUUGGUUUGCUGUUGGGAGCAGCAUUUAGUAGACGUAUUUUUGAGCACUUGUUAAAUAGCGCAUCUGUUGACAGAAUUGAGAGUAUUCAUUUUACAUAUACCUUUAAUCAAAUAAUGGAAGCUGGCUGUCGUAAAACUUUCCCACUGGUUUCCCAAGCAGUCUGCCUGUUCAGGCCACACAUCAUUCAUUUCUUUAGUUAGUUUCUAACCAUCCUGAUGGCAAACUUCUGAAAAUAACACUGUAACAUUCACUUACUUGGAGCUCAAGUUUUACAGCUUAGGUAUGAAACACAUAAGGCAGGAGGAAGUUACUGGAAUCUGUAGAUUUCCUUCUGUUCCCAUGCCCUGACCUAAGCAAUUUUAUAUUCAUUGUUUACAUCUAAUCAUCCAGUAAAACCCUGUGAGGUAGAAGAUAAGGAAACUUAAGACUAUACCAUUAAGAAUUAGGAAGUAAAGUUCAAACAAAGAACACCUUUGAGCAUCCAUAUAAAUGCCAAAGUCCUAGCACUAAAGACUAUUAUGUAUCUGAUGCAUAAGAGAAUAAUUAGGUUAUCACCCAGAACCUACUUGUUGUUACUUUAUACCUAGUAGUAAACUUGAUAGUUUAUUUCCAAACAAUUUUUAGGGGUAAAAGGAUGCUGCUGCAGGCAGGCACAUAGGCAGUAGUGAUCAGCGGGGGACAACUAUGCAGGGGAAGAAAGAGGCAGAAAAACGGCCAGGCGCAGUGGCUCAUACCUCUAACCCCAGCACUUUGAGAGGCUGAGGCAGGCGGAUCACUUGAGGUCAGGAGUUCGAGACUAGCCUGGCCGACAUGGCAAAAUCCCCUCUCUACUAAAAAUACAAAAAUUAGCCAGGCGUGGUGGCUUACGCCUGUAAUCCCAGCACUUUGGGAGGCAGAUGCAGGCGGAUCACUUGAGGUCAGGAGUUCGAGACCAGCCCGGCCUACAUAUCAAAACCCCGUCUCUACUAAAAAUUCAAAAAUUAGCCAGGUGUCGUGGCGCACGCCUGUAAUCCCAGCCAUCUCAGGAGGCUGAGGCAGGAGAACGGCUUGAACCUGGAAGGCAGAGGUUGCAGUGAGCCAAGAUCCACGCCACCUGCACUCCAGCCUGGGUGACAAAGUUGAGACUUCAUCUCAAAAGAAAUAAAGAGAGAAAGAAAAGAAAAGAAAGAAUAUGCAGUGCUGAUAGAAGAAUUCAGAGUUCCACAUUACAGGGCUAUUGAAUUCAAGGAAUACUCCCCUGAAUUCAUAAUAGCCUCUGAGAGCAGGUUAAUACAUAUAAUGACUCCAGGUCCUCAGAAAUCUUUUAAAAAAUUAUUCAGUUAAAUUGAGGAAUUUGUGAGAGAGACAAAAUUCUGGACUCAAAAUCUUUACUGAAUAUAACUCAGAAAUCAAAAUACUAUUCUACCUGAGUACUACUUCUGGUGGCUAAAUUGAUUGUUUCUUAUUCAUUAUGGUCUUGCUGGGAAAUUCCUAUGUUUUUUUUUUUUUUAAUUUGUAUGUGUUAAGAGUUAAGUGUAAUAAGAUACUCAGUAGGUAUUCACCCAUUGGUGCUUAUUUUGGGAGCUAAUUCAUACAGUUAGAAUGUAUCAUUUCUUGCAACCUUGGUUGAAUCAUCAAGGUUUUCCCAUCUUGACUGUGUUGAGGUUUAUCCCAGCUUGACUUCCCUUCGUGUCUUAGCACAUCCUGGUCCACUUUCCCUGCUAUCAGUUGUUAAGUAUUUAGAGAAUGCUGUUAUUAUUAGCCUGAGUGAAACAUAGUUUAAUUUUUCAUAUAAAUAUGUAUGUGAAUACUUUUAAAAUUAUCUAGAUAAUAGUUGCUUUCUUGUAGAGACUUGGAAAUAAAAGAAUAAGAUUGCAUUACUACUGAAAUACUUUGUUUCAUCCUUCAUCUCUUUUUCCUUCAACCCCAGCUGUUCAUUUGGUUACUAUUUUGCCAUAAACAGAGUACUGCCCUUUAUUCUUAGUGGAUUUAAACUAUCUAAUUUCAUUAGAUCUUUAAAUCUUUGAUGCAAAUAUUGACAAUUUGUUCUUCAACCAAAAAAGAUUAGGUAAAUAUAUAGUCCAGAAUAUUUAUGCUGCUAUUUCUUGAUUGUUUAAAACCCAGAAGUAAUGUUUGUCAGAGGAUCACUACCAUUGAGACUAAAAAGUAGUAAACUUUUCUAUGCCUUUAGUGAAAUUUUAGGUACUUCAUUUUAAAAAGUUUUGUUGUGCAGUAUACAAUACAUUUAAUCACGUGACAGAUUUGUGCAAAUUUGUAGGAAACCCAAGUUCUGCUUAUAAAUUACUUUUUCCUCUUUCUUUACAGUGAUGGAUUAAGCCGGUUUGAUGCAAUCAGACUUUUUGAUGACUUUCCUAGACGUUAAAAGUGUGAAGUGUCCUUUGGCUUAAAAUAUUGAGACUAUAAUUGUAACAUCAUCCAGGUUCAGAACUGAGUACUCAUUUUUUUUUCCAAUUUAAUGUCAGUAUAAAGUAUUAUCACUUACAUUAAAAUUCUUGGGACAAGGGUAAACAACAGCAGGGUUUUGUAGCUUACUUUUGUUAUAUUAGUCAAUAAACCUAUUUUGUAAAUCCUGUGUGACAGUGUGGGAGGUGGGGGCAGAAGGGUUCAGAAAGAACAUUUCGUUUUUAAGGCAGUAAUAUGAAAAUAUUUUGAGAUGAAUGUUGUUACUAAUGUGUGUUUUCUUAAUUCUUAAACUGGGACACAUUGACAAUUAUGGCCUCAUAAAUGAAAUGAGAGAGGGAAUGAUGAUAGUAAUUGAGGGUUUUUUCUUCAGAAAUUAUAGUUUGUUUUUCCUUUAAUAUUUGAAACUGAUAAAAGUCCAUUUAUCGUCAGUAAAGUGUAAAGGAAGCAUAUAACCUUUUAGGGGAGACAGUGUGGUAUAGUGACAUGAGCACAAAUCUUGUUUAAUAAAAUGUUUCUUGAAUGAAUAAACACCUACUAUGUGCCAGGCACUGUACUAGGCAAAUAAUAGGCACUGGCACUUAAUCUAGGCUUAAGGAACAAGGAAAGCUUUCCAUAAGUGACCACAGGAGGACGAAUAGGAAUUUGAUAACGGAGAUGCAUCAGGUUGAGUUUGACAUUGAAUGUUCAAAACUGGGAAAUAAAAUUCAUGCCAUGAAUUUAGAGCAAGAGUAUAUUCCUAAGGGGUGAAGAGGGGAGGGAAAAGAGGCUGAUUAGAGGUGUCAGGAGGUUGUAGGCAGAUCAUAAACACCUUAUUUCAGGUCAGUGGGGAGUCAUCAAAACAAUUUAAGAAGCAUUAUAAGAUUUGCCUUUAGACAGACUUGGACCAUUCUCAACUUCAGAGCUCUCAAAAUUAUCUCUGGUGAAAGGCUAUUUUAAAAAUUUUUAAUAAGUGGCCAACUGAUAACUUUGGAAAAUACAACCACAAUGAAUUACUAGAAGAAUGAAAUGUUUGAAAGAUAAAACUAUGCUGGCUCAUGCAUAUAGUCCUAACUACUUGGCAGGCUGAGGUGGGAGGAUCACUUGAGCCUGGGAGGUCAAGGCCGCAAUGAGCCAUGAUCAUGCCACUGCACUCCAGUCUGGAUGACAGAGCAAGACCCUGUCCCUACAACCCCCCGCCAAAAAUAAAAAAUAAAAACAAGCCCACUUUUAAAUUAGAUUGAACAGACUGGGCACAGUGGCUCACACCUGUAAUCUUAGCACUUUGGGAGUCUAAGGUGGGAGGAUUGCUUGAGAUCAGUCGGGGCAACACAGUGAGACCCCCAUUUAUACAAAAAAUUUUUUUAAAUGAGCCAGAUGUGGCAGCACACAUCUGUGGUCCCAGCUACUCAGGAGGCUGAGGCAGGAGGAUCACUUCACUUGAGCCCAGAGGUCAAGGCUCUAGUGAGCCAUGUUCUUGCUGUGCACUCCAGCCUGAGUAACAGAGCAAGACCCUGUCUCAAAAAAAGAUUGAACAUUGAAUAGACAUAAAAUUGCUCUAGUUUCUCUAUAAAAGUUUCUAAGUGUGUACUCUCAAAUUUAUUCUGUUCUAGUCAUUAACUACUUCACUUUGAGUACCUCUGUUACAGAGGAGUAAUGUUUUUUUGGUCCUGCAUGCUCUCAGUACAGAACUCUAGAGCCUCCCAUGUAUAUAUUUACUUUUCAGCCUUACCCAUGUACUGCUGUUCAGUUAUAUGGUUUCCAUUAUAAACCAUAAAAUAAUAAGUUAGAAAAAGUAAGAAAAUAAUGAGAGGUUGGAUAAGCUAUUAUAAAAUGUAAAAUUUUAUUUUUAAUAGUAUAUAAAUGUUGUGUUGGCACUAAACCAUUGUUUAGUGAGAUCAGUAUAACUGAGUAUUCCUGUUAGCUUAUGAACAGAUUCUUAUUUAUUUAUUUUGGGGACAGGGUCUCACUGUGUCACCCAGGCUGGAGUGCAGUGGCACAGUCAUGGCUCUUUGCAGCCUCGACCUCCCGGGCUCGAGCAAUCCUCCCACCUCAGCCUCCCAAGUAGCUAGGACUACAGGCAUGUGCCAGCAUGCCCAGCUGAUUUUUGUAUUUUUUGUAGACACAGAGUUUUGCCAUGUUGCCCAGGCUGGUCUCGAACUCCUGCGCUCAAGUGGUACACCCCCCUUGAUCUCCCAAAGUGCUAGGAUUACAGGCGUGAGCCACCACGCCUGGCUGCAGAUUGUUUCUAGUGGAAAUCCACAUAGCUUCUCCGCUCAUGAGGCUUACUCUGUGAUUGUUUCUGAUCAAAAGGUUCUGUGUCUAUCCUAGGUGUAUUGUGUAUCCUGUAACUAAAACUUGAGGUAUUGUUGGAAACAUUUGAAACAAUGUAGGUCUGGAGUUUCAUAGUCCUGCAUUUGAAUUCCAGCUUAUUGUUGUGUGAUCCCGGACAUGUUUGCACUGGACUGAAUGUUUAUGUUCCCCCCAAAUUUGUAUGUUGAAAUCCUAGACCGCAAGGUGAUGGUAUUAGGAGUUGGGGCCUUUAGGAGGUAAUUAGGUCAUGAGGGAAGAGACCUCAUGAAUGGAAUUGGUGUCCUUAUUGAAAAAGACCCCAAAGAGAUCCCUUGCUCCUUCCACCAUGUGAGGUUACAGUGAGAACACAGCCAUCUAGGAGGAAAUGGGUCCUCACCAGACACCGAAUGUGCUGGCACCUUGAUCUUGGACUUCCCAGACUCCAGAACUGUAAGAAAUAAAUUUUUGUUGUUUAAAGAAAGAAUGAAAAUUUCUUCCUGCUUUUCAGUGUUAUUAUUGAAAACAGAGAUAACUUUUCAAGUAUCUGUCAUAAAGUCUUAGAUCUAUUUUAAGCCCUUAAGUAAGUGUCUGUUUCAUUUUGUUUCAACAACUGCAUCAGCUGGUAUGCCACUUCUAUAUGGUAUAACAUUUUUCUCAGGAAGUCAGAUUUAUACUUCCCUAUUAACACACCUUUAUAGAGGCUGUCAUCAUGUAAGCUUCUAAAGUCAUAUACAAAAUUUUGGAAUUUUGUAGGUUUUACAGGGGCCCAGUGGCCUGGGUUCAGUCCUCUCAUUUUACAUAUCUGAAAACCAUGGUCUUCAGAGGUUUGUAGUGGCAGAAAACCGAAAUCUUUAGAGCCUAUUAGGUGGUAGAACCUAGGCCCAUUGACUUAUACUCUAGUCCUCUUUCUGCUAUCAUGUGUAAUCCAGAGCUUUAUGUUUAAAAACAGUGUGAAAAUGAAAAAGGAGUUAAUAUAUACAGUUUGUUUUGCCAGUAAGUUUUCCAUCAACUUAAUAGCUUUUUUUUUUUUGUCUCUUUUCACAGUUAACUCUUUCGUCCAGCAGAUAUUAAGGGCCUCAUGUGUCAGGCACUAUCUAAGGUAGUGGAGAUACAACAGUAAAUACAAUGGGCAAAAUUCUGCCCUCAUGGAUCUUAUGUUCUGCAGAGAGGAGUCCUAAAGGAUGUGAGGGAGUGAGCCAUGUGCUAAUCUUCCAGUAGAAGGAAUGGCAAAGUAAUUUAGGAUCUCUUAGACCUCAUAAGGCUUUUAUUCCCAGUGAUAUGAGAAGUCUUAGGAAUGGCUGUAUUUUGAGAGUAGAGGUGACAGAUUUGCCAGCCAAUCAGUUGUGGGCUGUGAAAGAAGAGUUAAGAAUGACUCCAAGGGGCCAGGUGCAAUGGCUCACCCCUGUAAUCCCAGCACUUUGGGAGGUCGAGGCAAGCGGAUCACUUGAGCCCAAGAGUUUGAGACAGUAGAGGCAAUAAGUCAAAAUCCAGUAUCUACAAAAAAUACAAAAAUUAGCUGGGCAUGGUGGCAUGCGCCUGUAAUCCCAGCUACUCAGGAGGCUUGAGGUGGGAGGAUCGCUUGAGCCCAGGAGAUCAAGGCUGUGCUGAGCUGUGAUCAUGCCGUUGCACUCCAGCCUGUGCGACAGAGCGAGACCCUGUCUCAAUAAAAAUAAAAGAAUGACUCCAGGAGUUUCAGUGUGAGCAACCUAAAGAAUGAGGUUGCCAUUUACUGAUAGAGGGAAAGCUAAGAGAGAAGCAGGUUGGAGUAGGUUAAACCAGGCAUGGAGUUUUGGACAGUUUGGAAUUUGGACAGUUAAGUUGCCUAUUAGACAACUAGUUUUAUGUGUUAAGUAGGCAGUUACAUGUGAAUCUGAUGUUCAGGGGAGAGAUGAAAUCCAGAGAUAUAAAUUUGGAUGUCAUCCCCAUAUAGAUGCUAUACUGAGUAUUAUGGUUUGAAUGUUUGUGUUGCCUCCAAAAUUCAUGUUGAAACUUAAUCCUUAAUUCAACAAUAUUAAGAGAUGGUGCCAAUAGGAGGUGAUUAGUUCACGAGCGCAGAGUCCUCAUGAAUGAGAUCAGCAACUUUAUAAAAAGGCUAAAGGAACUAGCUAGGCCCUUUUUUGCUCUUCUGCUCCUUUUCCUAGUGAGGACACAGCAUUCGUCCCCGCUGGAGGAUGCAGCAACAGGGUGCCAUCUUGGAGCAGAUGAUGGUCCUCACCAGACACCGAACCUGCUUCAAUUUGGACUUCUAGGCCACAGAACUAUGAGAAAUAAAUUUCUGUUCUUUAUAAAUUACCCAGGCUUACAUGUUUUGUUACAGCAACUCAAACAGCCUAAGUGAACUCAUGAAAGGAAUGAAUGUAGAUAGAAAAAAGAGGCCCAAAAAGAGAUGGAUGGAAAAAGAGAAGCCAUAAUGACUUUGGAAAACCAGGUGAUUGUGGUAUCCUGGAAACCAAAUAAAGAAAAUGUUUUAAGAAAGAGGGAGUGAUGAUCUGGGUCAGCUGCUACUGAUAAGUGAGGUAUAACGAAGAUUGAAAAUUGACUGUUGGAUUUAGCAGUGUGGAGGUGACCUUAACAAAAGCUUUAUAUGAGUAGGCUUGGGAGAGAAUAAAAGGAACAGAAUUGGAGACAGUGAGUUUGAGAAAUGAAGUAGGGUUGAGAGUUUUUGUUUUAUUUUUAAGAUAGAAAAAAAUACAUUUGAAUCCAGUAGAGAGGAACAAAUUCAUGGAUGAAAGGGGGAGAAUUUCUGGAGCAGUCUCUGUUGAGUUGGCUAGAGGGAAUGAGAUCGGCAUGAGUGGAAGCAUCGGGCUUACUAGGAUCUUGAUCAGUUUCAUUUAUAGCAGGGGUUGGCAAACCCCAGCUCUGGAGCCAAAUUCAGCCUGCUGCCUGUUUUUAAAAUAAAGUUUUGUUGGAACAUAACCUUGUGCAUUUAUUUAGGUAUUGUCUGUGACUGCUUUCAAACUAUGGCAGCAGAGUUGAGUAGUGCUGCAGAGAAGCCUAAAAUAUUUACUAGAAAGAGUUUGCCAACCCUUAGAUUUACAGUAACUGAAGAAAAGAUAGGAUGAAAUAUGAGUGGGAGAGGGGAAGAAAUAGGUAUCAAAUCUAGGGAAUUGAACAUUUUGAAGAAGGUAGUAAGACCCCUUUUCUGGUUUUGGUCAAACCACAUAGAAAAUCAGAACUUUGAAUUUAGACUUGCAGUCUCGGUGCUUUUUCCUAAGGCGGGUUCUUGGAAGGGGCCCUAGUCUCAAACUGUAAGCUAACUAUAUAGUUAUCUAUUGGGGCUGUGUUAUAAAUUACCAAUAUCUUAGCUGCUUAAAACAACAAACAUUUAUUACCACAGUUCCUGUGGGUCAGCAAUGUGAAAGCAGCUUAGCUGGAUGGUUCUGACUUAGAAUCUCCCAUGAGGCUGCAAUCAAAGUGUCAGCCAGGGCUGCAGACUUCUGAGACUUGGCUGGGUCUAGAGAGUCGGCUUCGUAUCUUAUUCAUGGCUAUUGGCAGGAGGCUUCAGUUCCUUGCCACAUCAGCCUCUCCUUUGGACUAGUCAUAAUGUGGCUUCCCCUGUAGAAAGUAAUGAGACAGAGUGCCCAGGACAGAAGCCUCAGCCUUUUAUAUCCUAAUCUUUGGAAGUGACAUGCCUUUACUUCUGUAUCGUAGACAGUCCCCGACUUAGGAUUUUUCAGCUUUACAAUGGUGUACCAUCAUUAUGUUUUUCACUUUCAACCCAGUAUUCAAUAAAUUAUAUGAGAUAGUCAACAAACACUUUAUUAUAAAAUAGGCUUUGUGUUAGUUGAUUUUGCCCAACUGUAAGCUAAUAUAAGUCUUCUGAGCAUGUUCAGGGUAGGCUAGGUGUAUUAAAUGCAUUUUCGACUUAUGAUGUUUUCAACCUAACAAUGGUUUUGUUGGGAUGUAACUCUAUUGUAUGUUAAGGAACAUCUGUAUAUUUGUCACACAGACCGACCCUGGUACAACAUAGAAGCCCACAUAAGGGCGUGAAUACUAGGAUGUGUGGGGAUUGUUGGAAGCCAUCUUGGAGGCUCCUCACCACACUGAUCCACUUGAGUGUCUGCAAAACUCCGUGUCAUGUGACCAGUGUUUCUACAAUUGCUGAAGCAGCUAUUUGUGACAGUUUGAUUAUAUUGGAGCCUAACCACAAAUAUUUUAAAUAUUUUUCCUUUUUCACUAAGCUUUUUUUUUUUCCUGAUUACAAAAGUAACAUUUGUGGUAGAAAACUGGAAUACAGUUAGGCAGAAAGCCCUGGAAGUUAAACAUUUUUCAUAUUCCCUUGUUCAGAUUACUCUUAGUGAAAUUUUAUUUUGCUAUCUAAUUUUUUCAUGUUUGUAGUAAUACAUAUCUGUUCAAAAUAAAGUUAAUAUAUAAAUGCUGUUUGUAAGCAGCUUUUAUUUUCUGAACGUUUUUCAGUGUUAUUCAGUACUCAGUGUCAUUUUUAAACGACUGUUUUAUGGUUCAUGGCUAUCCAUAAUUUUUUACUAUGAUGAAUAAUGUUACAAUAAAUAUUCUUAUCGCUAAUUUUCUAUGGAUAAUCAUGACACUGAUAGCCAUUGUCUCAGUCCAUUUCCUGCUGCUAGAGCAAAGUACCACAGACUGGGUAAUUAGUAAAGAAUAGAAAUUUCCUUCUCAUAUUCUGGAGGCUGGGAGGUUUAAGAUCAAAGUAUCAGCAGAUUCAGUCUCUGGUUCCAAGAUGGUCCCUUAUUGCUGCAUCCUCUAGGGAGGAGGAAUGUGGUGUCCUCCUAUGGCAGCAGAGCAAGAGAGGGUGAAAGGGCAAGGUGAAAAGUGAUGAACCUGUCCUUUUAUAAGGGCACCAAUCCCACCCAUGAGGGUGGCCUCUUAUGGUUUACUCACUUCUUCAAGGUCCCACAUCUUAAUACUGUGGCAAUGGCAGUUAAAUUUCAACAUGAGUUGGGACAAACAUUCAAACUGUAAUAGCCAUUCCCCACCCCAUAUCAAUUCUUACUAAUAAUUCACAUACAAAUUCACCAAAAGUAAUAAUUGUAGGUAUAAGUUUUAUGAUAUUUGCAUUAGUUUUUAAACAGGACCAUAGUAGGGCUUCUAGGGAUGAAGGUCCGUUGGUUUUAUUGGGUUCUCAAGGAUGACUAGGAUAUUCAAAUCCUCAGUUAAUUUGCAAAAAUUGUUCAGUUGCUGUAAUCAUAGGAGUAACAUAAACCUGUUGGAGUGGAUAUAAGAAUAAAGCAAUUCUAAUAUUCCUCAGACUCCUAAACUUCAUAAUACCUGUAUAAGGUAAGAAGCAAGAAAAGUUUUACAGAGGUUUGCUACUUUCUAGAGUGAUUUUAGUAAAUGCCUAUCAGAGGAUUUGAAUUUCUUUGUAGUCAAAUCUUGAUGUAGUUGAAUUAAUUAAUUUUAUUAUUAUUAUUAUUAUUUGAGAUGGUCUGUUGCCCAGGCUGGAGUGCAGUGGUGUGAUCUUGACUCACUGCCACGUCUGCCUCCCAGGUGCGAGCAAUUCUCCCACCUCAGCUUCUCAAGUAGCUGGGAUUACAGGCAUGCACCACCAUACAUGGCUAAUUUUUGUAUUUUUAGUAGAGAUGUGGUUUUGCCAUGUUAGCCAGGCUUGUCUCAAACUAUUAUUAUUGUUAGCCAGGCUGGUCUCAAACUAUUAUUAUUAUUAUUAUUAUUUUUUGAGACGGAGUCUCACUCUGUUGCCCAGGCUGGAGUGCAGUGGUGCGAUCUCGGCUCACUGCAACCUCCACCUCCCAGGUUAAAGCGAUUCUCCUGCCUCAGCCUCCUGAGUAGCUGGGAUUACAGGCAUGCGCCACCAUGCCUGGCUAAUUUUUGUAUUUUUAGUAGAGAUGGGGUUUCACCAUGUUGGUCAGGCUGGUCUCAAACUCCUGACCUUAUCAUCCGCCUGCAUCAGCCUCCCAAAGUGCUGAGAUUACAGGCAUGAGCCACCACGCCCGGCCUAUUAUUAUUGUUUUUUGAGAUAGGGUCUUGCUCUGUCACCCAGGCUGAAGUACAGUGGCACAGUCAUGUCUCACUGCAGCUUUGACUACCUGGCUUAAGCCAUUCUCCUACCUCAGCCUUCUGAGAACUGAGACCACAGAUGUGUUCCACCAUGCCUGGCCAAUUUUUAAAACAUUUUUAGUAGAGAUGAGACCUUGCUAUGUUGCCCAGGCUGGUCUCAAACUCCUGAGCUCCUAUAAUCCUCCUACCUAGUUGUAAUAAUUUAUUUAGAAUAAUUUAUUUAGAAUUUAUUUAUUUAGAAUAAUUAUAUGAAGUGUCACCUCAGCUCAGCAGAAUUCUCCCUCACAAUUCCAUUUUAUUUUUUAGGACCUUUUUGAACAUUAGUCUUGUAGUAGCUUAUAGCUUCUGAGACCAGCAUUUAAUUUGUUUGUAGUACAUUGUACUUCCAGGUGAUAAAACAGCAUUAAGCAGAGUACCUAUUCCUCCUGGGUGGAUGUCUCAGAAUUUUGCCAAUACUGAUGAACUGUUCUCCAAAAUCAUUUUCUAGAGUUUAGGGUUUUUUUCCAUCUGAAUAUGUACUAGUUAUUUUCAUGUACUGUGCUAGAUGCUGAGAUUACAGAACUGAGAAAGAUAGCUCUCAGCUCCCAAUAAUUAAUUUGAUGAGUAGCACUGAUAGAAGUUAUAUCCAGAAUACUAGGGAACAAUGAAACAAGCCCAUUGAAGGCUGGAGAGCAAUUGGAAGGCAGAGGACACUGCACAGGGGGUUCUAUUUGAACAACUUUCUUUACCUUUAUGUACACAGUCACAUCACCCUAUCAGUAAAAAUGUUUUAAUUGAAAACAUUUUUAUUGAAUUGUAUGAAUCAAGAACAUAAUUGCUUCUUUCACCAUUGAAUAAUAUGUUAUCAAAUAUGCAUUAAAUUGGUCGUCUUAGAAAUGGCUAAAAUAUGUAUUUAUAGAAUAAGAAGGUAUUUGAAUUUAAUCAGCUCAGUCUCCAAUCCUCUUUCUUUAUCUGUUUGAAUUCUUUGAUGGGGCUUACAGACAGUUUAUUCCAGUUUUUACAGUAAUAAGUAAUUGGAAAGAUCUUGCUAGUGAGCCAAAUCUGCCUCUUUUUGUCUUCUCCUCAGUAAUUUUAGUUUUAAAUUGUAAAAAUUAUCUCCCAGUCUGUGACUUAUCCUUUCAUUUUCUUAACCUUCAAAGACUGGAAGUUUUUUAUUUUGAUGCAGUCCAACUUAUCAAUUUCAUAGAUUUUGCAUUUGACAUUGUAUCUAGGAAAUCAUCGAAUGCCUAACCCAAGGUCACAUGCCUAACUCUAUGCUUUCUUCUAGAACUUUUGUGGCUUUAGGUUUUACAUUUAGAAACAAUCCAUUUUGAGUUAAUUUUUUUGUAUAUGGUGUAUAUGUGAAUCUAAAUUUUUGUUUGUUUGUUUGUUUGUUUGUUUGAGAGAGGAUCUUGCUCUGUCACCAAGGCUGGAGUGCAGUGGUGUGAUCAUGGCUCACUGCAGACUCGCUUUCCCAGGCCCAAGCAGUUCUCCCACCUCAACCUCCCAAGCAGCUGGGGCUAUAGGCGUGUGCCACACUAUACCCAGCUAAUUUAGUUUUUGUAGAGACUGUAUCUCACUAUGUUGCCCAGGCUGGUCUUGAACUCCUGAGCUCAAGCAAUCCUCCUGCUUUGGCCUCCCAAAAUGCUGGGAUUAUAGUCAUGAGCCACCACGCCCAGCCUCUAAAUUCUUUUUUUGCAAUUGUAUUUUUGCAUCUAAUUGUUCUAGCAUCAUUGUUUAAAAAGUGAUUCUUUCUUUACUGAAUUGCCUUUUGCACCUUUGUCAGCAGAUGCUGAAAACUACAAACCACUCAAAUGUCCAUCAACAGGUGAAUGAAUAAACAAAUUGUAAGAUAUCCAUACCAUGGAAUACUACUCAGCAAUAAAAGGGAAUGAGCUAUAGAUACAAGCAACAGGGAUAAAUGUCAAAAUUAUGCUUACUGAAAGAAGCCAGAUAAAAGAGUACAUGUUGCAUAAUUCCUUUUAUGUGAAACUGAAGAAAGUACUAACUAAUCUAUAUUUACAGAAAGCAGAUCAGUGUAUGGAGGGGAGAUGGAGGGAAAGGAAAGGGAGGGAUUACAGUUGAACAGGCUUAAAUAUGUGCAGUUUGUCGUAUGUUGUACCUCAAUAAAGCUGCUCCAAAUAUAAUUCUAAAAUUUAUAUAGAAUAACAUAGUGGCUAGAUAAGCUUUUGAUAACCAAGGUUUUUCUUUUCCCAUUUCUUAAUUUUUUUUCAUACUGUAACUCCAGUUUAUUGUUCUUCUUAAAAAGGUAUGUAGAUCUGAAUAUAGCAUUUGGAAAAUAAUUGAUUGUUGUAAACUCACUUCAAGUAUAUCUUCUGUUUCUUUGAGUUAUGUCAUGCCAGUCCCUACAGAGUCUGUUAACCUUACUUGGUAUCAUUGUUUCACUUUGCUUAUUAUAAUUUAACCCAAACUUCCCCAAAUUUUCCACAAUUAUAUUAUUAAUAGAAAUUACAGAAUACAUCAGGAUCAAGGCAUAUAAGGAUUAAGGGGAGAGGAGUAAAAAAAGAAAUGCGCAGGGGCAGAAUUAAGGAAUUUAGAUUUUCACCUAUGAGCAAUGUGGAGUCUCUGAAGAAUUUUAAGUAAGCUGAGUUAAACUAAUUUCACUUUUUAUUGUGAUCAGCUGAACUUACAUAAAAAGGCAGGCAGUAUUUAUCUAAGGGGAUUUGCAUCAGUCCCUUUGGUGUUUUAGUGAGUAUAUAGUUUUUUUGUAGUGGCAGAGUCAAAACCCCUAUUCAGAUAUCUUAAAUUUAUUCCCAAGCCUUGUACAUUAUAGUUGCAUCCUGUCAAGUGAACUGUAACUAGCAAUUCAAAAUUCAGAGUUACUUGAAUGUUCUUGUUUCUGAGUAUUUCUUGGGUUUAUGAGAUUGACAACUCUAUUUAGGCCAGAGUAUUUAGUCUACUGGAAUUAAGCAAAUACAGGUCCCAUCUAUUCAUGUUUGCUAUUUCUCAAUUUAAAAUCCUAUAGCAUGUAAGAGCAUUAGCAUUUUAUUUGUCUUUCUUUCAAUCCUUUAGAGUUAAGACUCACUAAUUUGGGAUUAGUUAUGACUCUAUGAGGCUACUACUGAUUUUUGAUAGGAACAAGAACCCAGGAAAGGAAAAAAAGGUAAUUUAUGAGCUGCAGCCAAUUAUCUGGCAACCAGAAUGCCUUGUUGUUAAGAGUCUAUUGUAACAAGUUUCUUUGUCUUCAUACAGCACCUGUUACUGUGCAACAAGACCGUGUUUUUGAACACCUGGCAUAACAUGAAACUGUUAGGUUAUAUUGUGGCUAAUCCUGAAGGAAGUUAGUUGAACUCUGGCUCAUUUAUUUAAACUCAGUCCUCCAGCAUGACAGAUUGGUGAAUGUGGAAGUGGGUACCAGUUACUAAGUAAAACAAACAUGCUCAGCCCAUCUCUUGAUCUGGACCCUGGAUUUUGGGAUAAAGUGAAGGGAUGAGGGUAAGGGAUGUUCACUUCAGAAGUCAUUGGGGAGUUUCCAGUGAUGUCACAUCUGACUACCCUGGCAUGGAUAUAUAGAAUCUCUUGGAUCAUACCAUCCUGGCUCUGUUCCAGUUUUGUUUGUUUGUUUGUUUUUGUGUUUUUUUGUUUUGUUUUGUUUUUGAGACGGAGUCUUGCUCGGUCACCCAGGCUGGAGUGCAGUGGUGUGAUCUCGGCUCACUACAACCUCCACCUCCCGGGUUUAAGCGAUUCUCCCGUUCAGUCUCCCGGGUAGCUGGGAUUACAGGCACCUGCCAUCAUGCUCAGGUAGUUUUUGUAUUUUUGUAGUGACGGGGUUUCACCACGUUGGCCAGGCUGGUCUUGAACUGCUGACCUCAGGUGAUCUGCCCACCUCGGCCUCCCAAGGUGCUGGGAUUACAGGUAUGAGCCACCACGCCCAGCCCAGUUCAUUUUAACUCCACCACAACUCUCUGGAACUUCAUGCCAGUGAUGUAACUCUUAUCGAACCCUUAUUUCCUCAUAUAAAAAAUGAAGGGUUUGGAUUAUUUUAAGGCUUCCUUCUGUGAUUCUUCAAUUUCAUUAUGUUUACUUUUAAAAAUUGUUCAAUGAAACUUCUAGGUAAACAUAAAAGCAACUUGUUAAAAAUUGUAAAAUGGAAAGAAAUAGACUAGUAUACUGAAGGAUAUUGUAUUGGAGACGGUCCCAGGAAAGCCCUACUUUCUGUGGGGUCUGGACCUUCUAAACAUUAUCUUUUUGGUCAUUAACCUGUCCUCUAUAUUAAUUGAGGCCUGUAAGCCUUAAGUGAUAAUGAAAUGCAGCCAGACAUGGUGGCUGACACCUGUAAUCCCAGCACUUUGAAAGGCUGGGGCAGGAGGAUUGCUUGAGCCCCGGAGUUAAAGAUCAGCCUGGGCAACACAGCAAGAGCCUGUCUCCACAAAAAAAGAAAAAAAAUGUUAAUGAAAUGCUACAAUUCUGCUUCCAACCACUAGUUUGAAUGUAGGUGCAUGUGUUUAGUAUUUCAAUUUUAAAUAUGAUUGUCUUUUAAUGAUAGUUUUAAAAGACUGGAGGUUUACUUGUGCAUGGGCCUGAUGCCCAGCCUGUGUGAUACUAGUUCAUUCCUGAUGAGCCAUGACUGUACCCACUAAGCCCCUUAAAGAGAGGGUACUCUUCCUCCUACUUCUCUUUCUUUGAGUUAAGAGUAUUAAUAGCACAUGCAUUCUAGUCCGUAUUCUUGAUGUUAAGACAUGUUGGAAAUGACUGAGGAGCGUUGUCCCUUUCUUGAGCACACAGACAGUUGCUAAAUGCAGGGCUUGUCUUAAAUUAAUGUUCUCUGGUGUCUUCUAUUACCAUCUCACUCCAUCAUUAACCCCAGUGGUCUUCAUCCUAGACAUAACAGUGGUUUGCACUGUGGCAUCCAUGACUUUGCUCCUUUUUCUCCUUCAGCUGCCUCUCCAACCCUCUCACCUCCCCCUACAAAGUCUGGGUAUAUUUUUGCCCAUUUCUUGCCUAGUGUUAUCAAUACUUCGAACAACUAGUAUAAAGAACUUAGUGAAGAGCACUGGUGCAAAGUAGUAUGUUCAGUCUGUUGGAUAUUUUUAUCCCCUAGCCACUUUCUAUUAGAUAAACCAUAUGAAACUGCUGUUUUUGUAUGUAUAUAUAUAUAUAAUGUUUGCAGUUUUAUAUGGUUUCACUUUAUAAAUAUACACAGUGAUGAUUUUUAACCAGAGAUAUGAACUACAGUUACCUAGGCAGUUUUUUACAAAAUAUAUAUAUACACACACACUGUCUGCAUCCUUGACCAGUGAAUUAGGAUCUUCAUGGAUGGUUCCAGAGUAAAUGCAUUUUUUAAAAACCUGAUUCUGAGUCAUACUCCUGGUUAAAAACACCUGUAAGCGAAUCUUCCCUCUAGGCUAUUUUUAGUUUUUUUAUUUUAAUUUUUUUUAGGGAUGGAGUCUUACCACGUUGCCCAGGCUGGCCUCAAAAUCCUGGGAUCAAGCAAUCCUCCCACCCUAGCCUCCUGAGUAGCUGGAACUACAGGCGUGCGCCACCGAGCCUGCCUCAAGCAGACUGCAUACAGAUGCAUAUGUUUUUGGUGUAAUCAGUUGUCUGAUAUGAACUGAAACUUUUAAGUCUAUGACUUCAUAAAUUGCUAUUAUUUAAAAUUUUAAGAUAUGGACCGGGUGUGAUGUCUCAUACCUGUAAUUCCUGCGCUUUGGGAGGCCGAGGCAGGCAGAUCACUUGAGCCCAGGAGUUCCAGACCAGCCUGGGGCAAAAUGGCAGAACCCCUCUAGAAAAAAACACAGCGAAAAAAUUAGUCAGGUAUGGUGGUGCUGCUGUGGUGGGGAUGAAAUGGUCUGAGGCAGGAGGAUUGCUUGACCCCAGGAGGUCAAGGCUGCAGUGAGCUGAGAUUGCAUUGCACCACUACCCCUCAGCCUGGGCAAGUGAGAGAGACUCUGUCUCAAAAAUAAAAAAUAAAUAUGAUCAAAUCUUAAAUUUAGAUUUUUCAGUACUCUUAGGAAGAAAAAUAUAAGUGCUACAAGAUGUUUUAUGAUUUUCAGGGAAUUGUCAAGUCUUUUUUUUUUCCCCUAGUUUGUAACUUCACGUUAUGUUUUGUAUAACUUCAACUUAAGAUUUUUUACUUUUCAGAUACACUUUUAUCUUUCAUGAAAAGGAGUUAACAGUAGUGAGCAGGCUGUAGUUCGUUAUUAACUUAAUUAUGACUCACAAUGCAGCUUACCCUACAUGAUUCGUAAUUUUAUCGUAGCCAAGAGAAAAUGGAGUUUCUUUGAACAGCAUCUGUCUCCCUUCACUGCUGGUAAUUUGUGUGUUAUUAUUAAUCACUGUUUUUGGAAUCUCUGGGUAAAUAGGCACUAAAUAAGCCCAAAAAUAUGAGCAAAAGUUGUCUGUUAAUUCAUUGGCCACUGCAGAAAGGAGUACUAAAGCCCAGAAAAGAGUUCUGAGCUUCCUUCUAUCUCUCACUAGCGUGUUCUCUCUAAUUUGCAUUCCUUAAAAAUGAGUUGCACUUGCUUUAGUGGCAUGUAUAUUUUUUAAAAAUACAGAUAAGUUUAGUGUGGCUCCUGUAUAAAAAUGACUCUCAAAAAAUAGUAAUAAAAGGAACAUGCUCUCCAAGGGAGCUAUGUGCAGCUCUUGGCCCUUGGAUGCCUGUGGCUGGGAGUCUGAAUCUGUCUGCCCAUGGCCCCCUCUUUAAAAAAAUUUUUUUUUUAAUUAAAAACAAUUUAAGGCCAGGCACAGUGGCUCACGACUGUAAUCCCAGCACUUUGGGAGGCCCAGGCAGGCAGAUCACAAGGUCAGGAGUUCAAGACCAGCCUGGCCAAUAUGGUGAAACCCCACCUCUACUUAAAAAGUACAAAAAUUAGCCGGGUGUGGUGGUGUGCACCUGUAGUCCCAGCUAGUUGGGAGGCUGAGGCAAGAGAAUUGCUUGAACCCAGGAGGCAGAGGUUGCAGUGAGCCAAGAUCACACCACUGAACUCCAGCUGGGGCAACAGAGACUCCAUCUCAAAAAAAAAAAAAAAUUGUAAAAUGACUCCCACUUGUGAUCCAUUUCUUUAGAAAUACAUAACACUUAUAAGAGGCAGUCUCUAGUGCUUAACUCAGAAGAAUUCUUAUCAAGAAGGAAUAUUGAAUUUUAUCCAAUGCUUAUUUCUUUUCUGUCUCUCUUUUUUUAAUGAAUUUGCCUUCUCUGCAUAACUUUUUCUUUUCACUUGCAUUGAUUAUAUUGAUUUUCUUAUUGGGCCCAUUCAUGUGAUUGUAUUUUUAUGCUUACUAUUAAUCUAAUAUUGCAUUUUUGGAAUACAGUUGACCCUUGAACAACACAGGUUUGAACCACAAUAGUUUACUUACGCAGAUUUUUUCAAUAAAUAUAUUGGAAAUUUUUUUACAGAUUUACAACAAUUUGAAAAAACUUGCAGGUGAGCUGUAUAACCUAGAAAUAUUGAAAACAAGAUAGGUAUAUCAUGAAUGCAUUAAAUAUAUGCAGAUACUAGUUUAUUAUUUACUAUCAGGUACACAAAUCUUAUAAAAAGUUAAAAUUUAUCAAAAUACAUGCAUACUAUAUUAGUCUGUUUUCAUGCUGCUGACAUGAAAGACAUACCCAAGAGUGAGUAAUUUAUAAAGAAAAAGAGGUUUAAUGGACUCAAACUUUUCCUGUGGCUGGAGAGACCUCACAAUCAUGGCAGAAGGUGAAAGGCAUGUCUUACAUGGUGGCAGACAAGAGAAUGAGAGAGCCGAGCUAAAAGGGAAACUCCUUAUAAAACAAUCAGAUCUCAUGAGACUUAUUCACUACCAAAAGAAUAGUAUGGGGGAAACUGCCCCCAUGAUUCAGUUAUCUCCCAGCGGGUCCCUACCACAAUACCUGGGAAUCAUGGGAGCUACAAUUCAAGUUGAGAUUUGGGUGGGUACACAACCAAACCAUGUCAUUCUGCCCCUGGCCCCUCCCAAAUCUCAUGUCCUCACAUUUCAAAACCAAUCAUGCCUUCCCAACAGUCCCUCAAAGUCUUAACUCAUUUCAGCAUUAACUCAAAAGUCCACAGUUCAGUCACAUCUAGACAAGGCAAGUCCCUUCAGCCUGUGAGUCUGUAAAAUCAAAAGCAAGUUAGUUACUUCCUGGAUACAAUGAGGGUGCAGGCAUUGGGUAAAUGCACCCAUUCCAAAUGGGAGAAAUUGGCCAAAACAAAGGGGCCAAAGGCCCUAUGCAAGUCCAAAAUCCAGCAGGGUGGUCAAAUCCAAAAUGAUCUCCUUUGACUCCAUGUCUCACAUCCAGGUCACUCUGAUGCAAAAGGUGGGUUCCCAUGGUCUUGGGCAGCUCUGCUUCUGUGGCUUUGCCAGGUACAGCCUCCCUUCUGGCUGCUUUCAUGAACUGAUGUUGAGUGUCUGUGGCUUUUCCAGACUCAUGGUGCAAGCUGUCAGUGGAUUUACCAUUCUAGGGUCUGGAGGACAGUGGCCCUCUUCUCACAGCUCCACUAGACAGUGUCCCAGUGGGGACUUUGUUGGGGGGCUUCAACCCCACAUUUCCCUUCUGCACUGCCUUAGCAGAAGUUCUCCAUGAGGGCCCUGCCCCUGCCUGGACAUCCAGGCGUUUCUAUACAUCCUCUGAAAUUUAGGCAGAGGUUCCCAAACCUCAGUUCUUGACUUCUGUGCACUCACAGGCUCAACAACACGUGGAAGCAGCUGCCAAGGCUUGGGGCUUGCACCUUCUGAAACCACAACCCGACCUGUACCCUGGCCCCUUUUAGUCAUAGCUGGAGUGGCUGGGAGGUAGGGCACCAAGUCCCUAGGCUACACACAGCAUGGGUUGGGGGGCCCUUAGCCCAGCUUUUGAAACCAUUUUUUCCUCCUAUGCCUCAGGCCUGUGAUGGGAGAGGCUGCCACAAAGGUCUCUGACAUACCCUGGAGACAUUUUCCCCAUUGUCUUGGUGAUUAACAUUGGGCUCCGGAGACAUUUUCCCCCGUUGUCUUGGUGAUUAACAUUUGGCUCCGCAGAUUUCUGCAGACGGCUUGAAUUACUCCUCAGAAAAUUGGCUUUUUUUUCCUAUUGCAUUGUCAGGCUGCAAAUUUGUCAAAGUUCUAUGCUGUUUCCCUUUUAAAACUGAAUGCUUUUAACAGCACCAAAGUCACCUUUUCAGUGCUUUGCUGCUUAGAAAUUUCUUCCACCAGAUGCCCUAAAUCAUCGCCCUCAAGUUUAGAGUUCCACAGAUCUCUAGUUCAGGGGCAAAAUUCUCAGUCUCUUUGCUAAAACAUAGCAAGAGUCACCUUUACUCCAAUUCCCAACAAGUUCCUCAUCUCCCAUCUGAGACCACCUCAGCCUGGAUUUCAUUGUCUAUAUAUCAUUAUCAGCAUUUGAGUCCAAGCCAUUCAACAAGUCUGUAGGAAGUUCCAGACUUUCCCACAUUUUCCUGUCUUCUUUGGAGCCCUCCAGACUGUUCCAAUCUCUGCCCAUUACCCAGUUCCAAAGUCGCUUCCACAUUUUUGGGUAUCUUUACGACAGCACCCCACUCUACCAGUACCAGUUUCCUGUAUUGGUCUGUUUUCAUGCUGCUGAUAAAGACACAUCCAAGACUGGGUAAUUUAUAAAGAAAAAGAGGUCUAACAGACUCACAGUUUCCUGUGGCUGGAAAGGCCUCACAAUCAUGGCAGAAGGUGAAAGGCACAUCUUACAUGGUGGCAGAUGAGAGAGUGAGAGAGCCAAGCUAAGUGAGACUUAUUCACUACCAUAAGAAUAGUGUGGGGGAAACUGCCCCCAUGAUUCAGUUGUCUCCCACUGAGUCCCUCCCACAACAUGUAGGAAUCAUGGGAGCUACAAUUCAAGAUGAGAUUGGGUGGGGACACAACCAAAUCAUAUCACAUACAAACACAACUAUAUGUGGUGCCAUUUGCAGUCAAGAGAAAUGUAAACCAAUGUAAAGAUUCAGUAUUAAAUUAUAACUGCAUAAAAUUAAGUGUAGUGCAUAUGAUACUACUGUAAUAAUUUUAUAACUACCUCCUGUUGCUAUUGUUGAGCUCAAAUGUUGCAAAUACCUACUUCAAAUGCCAUGUGACACUAAUUAUCUCUGUGUGAGCAGUUCAUCUCUCCAGUAAAUGUAGUGUUUGUACAACACUGUAAACUUUAAAUAACACUGUGGGACCCAUAAGAAAUGUUACUAGUGAUGCUGGAAGUGCUCCCAAGAAGCAGAGAAAAGUCAACAUUACAAGAAACAAGUUUAAUUGCCUGAUAUGUACCAUAGAUUGAGGUCUUCAGCUGUGAUUGCCCAUCAUUUCAAGAUGAAUGAAUCCAGAGUAAGGGACAUUGUAAAAAAAAAAAAAAGAAAAAAUAUAUGAAGCCUUCACUGCAGCUACAGCAGCAGGCACAAAAGCUUUGCAUUUGUUGCAAAAUACAUUUUUAUCAAAUUGAAAAUUCAGCUUUUAUGAGGGUGCAGGGUUGCUGUAAGAAAGGCAUACCUUUCCAAUCUGUCCCUGGGUCUAACGAAAAAAAGCCAUAGCUGUAGACUCCAAUGUGAUUCCAGAAAAAGCAGUGUCAUUAUAUGACAACUUAAAGCAAAAGGAAGGUGAAGGAUCUAAAGCUGGAGAAUUUAAUGCCAGCAAGGGAUGGUUUGAUAAUUUUAGAAAGAGGUUUGGCUUUUUAAAUGUCAAGAUAACAUGAGAAGCAGCUUCUGCCAACCAAGAGGCAGCAGGUGAAUUCCCAGAAGCCAUUAAGAAAAACAUUGAGGAGAAAGGAUAUCUGCUUGAACAGAUUUUUAAUGCAGACAAAAUUGCCCUUCUGGAAAAAAUUUUAAAAGCCACAAGGAACUUCUGUUGGUAGGGAAGAAAAGCAAGCACCAGGAUUUAAGGCAGGAAGGAAUAGGCUAACUACUAUUUUGUGCAAGUGCAGUCGGGUUUAUGAUCAGGGCUGCCCUUAUCUGUAAAGCUGCUAAUCCCCAAGUCUUGAAAGGAAGAGAUAAACACCAGCUGCCAGUCUUUAGGUUGUUGUACAACAAGAAGGCAUGGACAACAAGAACCCUUUUUCUGGAUUGCUUUCAUCAAUGCUUUGUCCCUGAAGUCAGAAAGUACCUUGCCAGUAAAGGAUUGGUUUUUAAAGUUCUUUUGAUAUUGGAUAAUGCCCCUGGCCACCCCAAACCCUAUGAGGUCGAAACUGAAGGCACUGAAGUAGUCUACUUGCCACCAAACACUACGUCUCUGAAUUCAGCUUCUAGAUUGGGGGUUGUAAGGACCUGGAAGGCUCAUUACACACAGCACUCUGUGGAAAGGAUGUCAGUACUAUGGAGGACCCCAAUAGAGGAACAUCAUGAAAGCCUAGAAGGCUCACACCAUUGAAGAUACCAUCAUUGUUAUAGAAAAAGCUGUGAAAGCCAUUAAGCCCCAAACAAUAAAUUCCUGCUGGAGAAAACUGUGUCCGAAUGUUGUGUAUGACUUCACAAGAUUUAUGACAUAGCCAGUCAAGGAAAUCUUGAAAGAGUUGGUGGACGUGCCAAAAAAAAAAAAUAGUGGGAGGGGGAACAAAAGUCUGCUUGAUAGAGAUCAAUGCUUCUGAACUGGUGCCAGGUGAUGAGAAAGGAGUCCUAGAAGAAGCAAACCCAUAAAACAAAGUGAUGUUAGAUAAUCUAGCAGAAGGGUUCUUAUUAUUCAAGACUGCUUUUGACUUCGUUUACAACAUAGACUCUUCCGUGAUACAAGCACUAAAACUAAAGCAAAUGGUGGAAGAAGGAUUGGUACCACAUAGAAACAUUUUUAGAAAAAUGAAAAAGCAAAAAAGUCUAAUUACAAUGCAUUUCUUUAGCUACAAUGAGUGUGCCUGCUUUUUCUGCCUCCUUUCCACCUCCUCCACCUCUUUUUCCUCUGCUACCCCUGAGACAGCAGGACCAAUCCUUCCUCUUCCUCCUCCUCUUCAGCCUACUCAACAUGAAAAUGAUGAGAAUGAAGACCUUUAUGAUGAUCCACUUUCACUUAAUGACUAAUUCUUCUUAAUCCUUUGGUGAAAACUGAGACACAAAAUGGCUGCAAAUAAGCCCAAGGGUCAGAAUUCUUUGGCUUUACACAAAGUCAUCAUGGUGGGCAGUGGUGGCGUGGGCAAGUCAGCUCUGACUCUACAGUUCAUGUACGAUGAGUUUGUGGAGGACUAUGAGCCUACCAAAGCAGACAGCUAUCGGAAGAAGGUAGUGCUAGAUGGGGAGGAAGUCCAGAUCGAUAUCUUAGAUACAGCUGGGCAGGAGGACUACGCUGCAAUUAGAGACAACUACUUCCGAAGUGGGGAGGGGUUCCUCUGUGUUUUCUCUAUUACAGAAAUGGAAUCCUUUGCAGCUACAGCUGACUUCAGGGAGCAGAUUUUAAGAGUAAAAGAAGAUGAGAAUGUUCCAUUUCUACUGGUUGGUAACAAAUCAGAUUUAGAAGAUAAAAGACAGGUUUCUGUAGAAGAGGCAAAAAACAGAGCUGAGCAGUGGAAUGUUAACUACGUGGAAACAUCUGCUAAAACACGAGCUAAUGUUGACAAGGUAUUUUUUGAUUUAAUGAGAGAAAUUCGAGCGAGAAAGAUGGAAGACAGCAAAGAAAAGAAUGGAAAAAAGAAGAGGAAAAGUUUAGCCAAGAGAAUCAGAGAAAGAUGCUGCAUUUUAUAAUCAAAGCCCAAACUCCUUUCUUAUCUUGACCAUACUAAUAAAUAUAAUUUAUAAGCAUUGCCAUUGAAGGCUUAAUUGACUGAAAUUACUUUAACAUUUUGGAAAUUGUUGUAUAUCACUAAAAGCAUGAAUUGGAACUGCAAUGAAAGUCAAAUUUACUUUAAAAAGAAAUUAAUAUGGCUUCACCAAGAAGCAAAGUUCAACUUAUUUCAUAAUUGCCUACAUUUAUCAUGGUCCUGAAUGUAGCGUGUAAGCUUGUGUUUCUUGGGCAGUCUUUCUUGAAAUUGAAGAGGUGAAAUGGGGGUGGGGAGUGGGAGGAAAGGUGACUUCCUCUGGUGUUUAUUAUAAAGCUUAAAUUUUAUAUCAUUUUAAAAUGUCUUGGUCUUCUACUGCCUUGAAAAAUGACAAUUGUGAACAUGAUAGUUAAACUACCACUUUUUUUAACCAUUAUUAUGCAAAAUUUAGAAGAAAAGUUAUUGGCAUGGUUGUUGCAUAUAGUUAAACUGAGAGUAAUUCAUCUGUGAAUCUGCUUUAAUUACCUGGUGAGUAACUUAGAAAAGUGGUGUAAACUUGUACAUGGAAUUUUUUGAAUAUGCCUUAAUUUAGAAACUGAAAAAUAUCUGGUUAUAUCAUUCUGGGUGUGUUCUUACUGACACCAGGGGUCCGCUGCCCCAUGUGUCCUGGUGAGAAAAUAUAUGCCUGGCACAGCUUUUGUAUAGAAAAUUCUUGAGAAGUAACUGUCCGCUAGAAGUCUGUCCAAAUUUAAAAUGUGUGCCAUAUUCUGGUUCUUGAAAAUAAGAUUCCAGAGCUCUUUGAUCGCUUUUAAUAAACUGCAAGUUCAUUUUAAAUGAAGGGCCAGCAUAUAUACUUGCAAGAUAAUUUUCAGCUGCAAGGAUUCAGCACCAGUUAUGUUUGAAUGAACCCUCCUUUUCUCUGAGAUUCUGGUCCCUGGAAAUCCCUUUCUGCUAGUGGUGAGCAUGUAAGUGUUAAGUUUUUAAUCUGGGAGCAGGGCAUAGGAAGAAAAUGUCAGUAGUGCUAAUGCAUUUUGCACUAGAACGCUUCGGGAAAAUAUUCAUGCUUGCCAUCUGUUCAUUUCUAAAUUUAUAUUCAUAAAGUUACAGUUUGAUACAGGAAUUAUUAGGAGUAAUUCUUUUCUGUUUCUGUUUAUAAUGAAGAACACUGUAGCUACAUUUUCAGAAGUUAACAUCAAGCCAUCAAACCUGGGUAUAGUGCAGAAAACGUGGCACACACUGACCACACAUUAGGCUGUGUCACCAUUGUGUGGUGUACCUGCUGGAAGAAUUCUAGCAUGCUACUUGGGGACAUAAUUUCAGUGGGAAAUAUGCCACUGACCGAUUUUUUUUUUUUCCUCUUUGCAGUGGGGCUAGGACAGUUGAUUCAACAAAGUAUUUUUUUCUUUUUUCUCAGUCCUAAUUUGAACAGGUCAAAGAUGUGUUCAGGCAUUCCAGGUAACAGGUGUGUAUGUAAAGUUAAAAAUAGGCUUUUUAGGAACUCACUCUUUAGAUAUUUACAUCCAGCUUCUCAUGUUAAAUAUUUGUCCUUAAAGGGUUUGAGAUGUACAUCUUUCAUUUCGUAUUUCUCAUAGGCUAUGCCAUGUGCGGAAUUCAAGUUACCAAUGUAACACUGGCCAGCGGGCCCAGCAAUCUCCAUGUGUACUUAUUACAGUCUUAUUUAACCAGGGGUCCUAACCACUAACAUUGUGACUUUGCUUUGAGACCUUUCCUCUCCUGGGUACUGAGGUGCUAUGAAGCCAACUGACAAAGAUGCAUCACGUGUCUUAGGCUGAUGCCACUACCCGAUUUGUUUAUUUGCAAUUUGAGCCAUUUAAAGACCAAUAAACUUCCUUUUUUAAAA